GUCUCACAGUGUCGCCGGGCUGGAGUGCAAUGGUGUGAUCUCAGCUCACUGCAACCUUCGCCUCCUGGGUUCAAGCGAUUCUCCUGCCUCAGCCUCCCAAGUAGCUGGGAUUACAGGCACCCGCCACCAUGCCUGGCUAAUUUUUUGUAUUUUUAGUUGAGACGGGGUUUCACUAUGUUGGCCAGGCUGGUCUCGAACUUCUGACCUCAUGAUCUGCCCGCCUCGGCCUCCCAAAGUGCUGGGAUUACAAGCGUGAGCCACCGCAUCCGGUCUGCUUAAGUAUUUUCUAUAUGAUAGAAAGUAAAAAUGCUCUGAGAGAAGCAAAACAUAAGGGGCUAUUGGGAGUUCACCGUGAACCCUUCAAAGCCUCCAACGCUGCUGAAUGACAACUAGAAGCUUAUUAAAUGUUUUGAGAGAAUUCUGGCAAGCUCAGAUGUCAGGUUCUCCACAUACGAUUCUACUUGUCAAAUUGCCCAAGAAAUUGCUGAGAAAAUUCAACAACGAAAUCAAUAUGAAAGAAAAGGUGAAAAGGCACCAAAGGUCCAGCCUGAUGAGUGAAGAGGCUAAGCGAGGAGCACCCAACCCUUGGCUCUUUGAGGAGCCAGAGGAGACCAGAGGCUUGGGUUUUGAUGAAAUCCGGCAACAGCAGCAGAAAAUUAUCCAAGAACAGGACGCAGGCCUUGAUGCCCUUUCCUCUAUCAUAAGUCGCCAAAAACAAAUGGGGCAGGAAAUUGGGAAUGAAUUGGAUGAACAAAAUGAGAUAAUUGACGACCUUGCCAACCUAGUGGAGAACACAGAUGAAAAACUUCGCAAUGAAACCAGGCGGGUAAACAUGGUGGACAGAAAGUCAGCCUCUUGUGGGAUGAUCAUGGUGAUUUUACUGCUGCUUGUGGCUAUCGUGGUUGUUGCAGUCUGGCCGACCAACUGAUGGCAGUAAAGAGACCACCAGCAGUGACACCUGCCAAUGACAGAUGCAAGCCCAACACCCUUUUGGUACGCAAAACCUGCUCUCAAUAAAUUCCCCCAAAGCUCUGA